GGCCACAGCCUGCCUACUGUCACCCGCCUCUCCCGCGCGCAGAUACACGCCCCCGCCUCCGUGGGCACAAAGGCAGCGCUGCUGGGGAACUCGGGGGAACGCGCACGUGGGAACCGCCGCAGCUCCACACUCCAGGUACUUCUUCCAAGGACCUAGGUCUCUCGCCCAUCGGAAAGAAAGGAAAACUACUAUCCAUCCCAGCCAGGCAAGCCCAAUUCAGGACUGAAGAAGAUUUAUUCAGUCCUAGACAACCAAGUGAAGAGUUUCUGGCUUUGUGCGCAUACAAGUCAUUUGCAGGAGAUGUAAGUCAGCGUGCUUUGGCCCUUGCAUUUCAGGAAGGUGACUGCUUUGUGGGGAAGAAAAAGGUGCACAAUAUGAGUAUUCUCUGGUUUGCUCAAACAGGGUAAAUUGGACAAGGAUUGAAAGGGAUGUUGCCAAGCUCUACAGUCAUUAAAUAUUUUUUUCCUCUAUGCUUUGUUUUAAAAACCUAGCUUCUCUAUUUUAUCCCACACUAACCUCCUCCUUCCCCACUCUAAGAAGUGACUAACGUUUCAGCCCUCAACUUUGUCAUUCAUAUAAUGGAGAUGACAAACUAUGUCUCACAGGGCUCUUGCAACAUUCAAAUGAGGUAAUAUAUGGCAAACACUUGGCAUAGUACCUUCCACAUAUUAAGGGUUCAAUAAAUGGAAACUUUUCUUAGUUUCUCUGUUUAUCAUUUUACAAGGACUUGUCCAAGAUUAAUAUUCUAAGAUCAUGAUUUUUAAACUUAUUUUUAAUGAUGAAAAUAUUCAUUACAUGAAUUUAGGGCAAACCCCCAGUAUAUGACAGGUAAAUGCAGGGCUGCUUUGGUUGAAGUGGGGUCACAAGGUCUAAAACUUACACCUUUGCUCUUAGCCUCUGGGACAUUGCCACAGAAUCUUCAAUGACAAAAAGCACAUUUACAAAUCAUGAAACCAGGCUGUGUGCAUUCUGGUUGCCAUUCUGCCCUUCAACAAGGAUUUUUGCCCCUCUGAGUCACCAUCUGUAGCAGAAGUAAGAGCAAGUCCACAAAUAGUGUAAUAGACAGGAAUAUGAAUGAGAAAUAAAAGACUUAACAAAGGCUAUUUUAAUUAAUUCUAAUGACAAUGAUAGCCAAAAUAUAUGAUGAGCCUACUCUCUAAACUGUAGGCUUUUGUGGGAUCAUCCACAGCAUGUCUCUGAGGUAUGGACUAUAUUUGUUGGACAAAGAGAUGGCUUCAAGAACAGGGAGACUGAAUAACUUUACCAAGGUCCUAGAACUCAGAGUGAUACAGCCAGGUUUCACACCCAGGUCCCCGUGAUCACCAAGUCAGAGGUACAUUCUGCCGUGUUCCUUCUGAAUGCUUCUCUGCUUCUUGCCUGCCUUUAGAAGGAAAACACUUCCUUUCUGACUAAAUAUGCCCCUCCAGGCAGACUGUGGCCACCCAUAAAUACAGCAGUAGCCUGAUCAUAUAACCAGAAUGGAAUUUGGAAAGAGAAUUCAAGCUGACAGAAUGAAAAACAUAUCCCCCUUAAUCCUACCCUUUCUAAUGCUAACAAUAAAUUAAGAGCACAUAUUCUCUCCUCUCUCUCUAGAUUUCUAUAGACACCUAGCUGUGCUUUCUUACAAGAAAACAUAUCCACUGGACCAAAGCGCAGCCCCCUUCAUGCUGAAGCCACUUCAGUUUGAAACGUAAAAAAAAAUAAUUCUUUCAAGAAGAUCAGGGACAACUGAUUUGAAGUCUACUCUGUGCUUCUAAAUCCCCAAUUCUGCUGAAAGUGAGAUACCCUAGAGCCCUAGAGCCCCAGCAGCACCCAGCCAAACCCACCUCCACCAUGGGGGCCAUGACUCAGCUGUUGGCAGGUGUCUUUCUUGCUUUCCUUGCCCUCGCUACCGAAGGUGGGGUCCUCAAGAAAGUCAUCCGGCACAAGCGACAGAGUGGGGUGAACGCCACCCUGCCAGAAGAGAACCAGCCAGUGGUGUUUAACCACGUUUACAACAUCAAGCUGCCAGUGGGAUCCCAGUGUUCGGUGGAUCUGGAGUCAGCCAGUGGGGAGAAAGACCUGGCACCGCCUUCAGAGCCCAGCGAAAGCUUUCAGGAGCACACAGUGGAUGGGGAAAACCAGAUUGUCUUCACACAUCGCAUCAACAUCCCCCGCCGGGCCUGUGGCUGUGCCGCAGCCCCUGAUGUUAAGGAGCUGCUGAGCAGACUGGAGGAGCUGGAGAACCUGGUGUCUUCCCUGAGGGAGCAAUGUACUGCAGGAGCAGGCUGCUGUCUCCAGCCUGCCACAGGCCGCUUGGACACCAGGCCCUUCUGUAGCGGUCGGGGCAACUUCAGCACUGAAGGAUGUGGCUGUGUCUGCGAACCUGGCUGGAAAGGCCCCAACUGCUCUGAGCCCGAAUGUCCAGGCAACUGUCACCUUCGAGGCCGGUGCAUUGAUGGGCAGUGCAUCUGUGACGACGGCUUCACGGGCGAGGACUGCAGCCAGCUGGCUUGCCCCAGCGACUGCAAUGACCAGGGCAAGUGCGUAAAUGGAGUCUGCAUCUGUUUCGAAGGCUACGCCGGGGCUGACUGCAGCCGUGAAAUCUGCCCAGUGCCCUGCAGUGAGGAGCACGGCACAUGUGUAGAUGGCUUGUGUGUGUGCCACGAUGGCUUUGCAGGCGAUGACUGCAACAAGCCUCUGUGUCUCAACAAUUGCUACAACCGUGGACGAUGCGUGGAGAAUGAGUGCGUGUGUGAUGAGGGUUUCACGGGCGAAGACUGCAGUGAGCUCAUCUGCCCCAAUGACUGCUUCGACCGGGGCCGCUGCAUCAAUGGCACCUGCUACUGCGAAGAAGGCUUCACAGGUGAAGACUGCGGGAAACCCACCUGCCCACAUGCCUGCCACACCCAGGGCCGGUGUGAGGAGGGGCAGUGUGUAUGUGAUGAGGGCUUUGCCGGUGUGGACUGCAGCGAGAAGAGGUGUCCUGCUGACUGUCACAAUCGUGGCCGCUGUGUAGACGGGCGGUGUGAGUGUGAUGAUGGUUUCACUGGAGCUGACUGUGGGGAGCUCAAGUGUCCCAAUGGCUGCAGUGGCCAUGGCCGCUGUGUCAAUGGGCAGUGUGUGUGUGAUGAGGGCUAUACUGGGGAGGACUGCAGCCAGCUACGGUGCCCCAAUGACUGUCACAGUCGGGGCCGCUGUGUCGAGGGCAAAUGUGUAUGUGAGCAAGGCUUCAAGGGCUAUGACUGCAGUGACAUGAGCUGCCCUAAUGACUGUCACCAGCACGGCCGCUGUGUGAAUGGCAUGUGUGUUUGUGAUGACGGCUACACAGGGGAAGACUGCCGGGAUCGCCAAUGCCCCAGGGACUGCAGCAACAGGGGCCUCUGUGUGGACGGACAGUGCGUCUGUGAGGACGGCUUCACCGGCCCUGACUGUGCAGAACUCUCCUGUCCAAAUGACUGCCAUGGCCAGGGUCGCUGUGUGAAUGGGCAGUGCGUGUGCCAUGAAGGAUUUAUGGGCAAAGACUGCAAGGAGCAAAGAUGUCCCAGUGACUGUCAUGGCCAGGGCCGCUGCGUGGACGGCCAGUGCAUCUGCCACGAGGGCUUCACAGGCCUGGACUGUGGCCAGCACUCCUGCCCCAGUGACUGCAACAACUUAGGACAAUGCGUCUCGGGCCGCUGCAUCUGCAACGAGGGCUACAGCGGAGAAGACUGCUCAGAGGUGUCUCCUCCCAAAGACCUCGUUGUGACAGAAGUGACGGAAGAGACGGUCAACCUGGCCUGGGACAAUGAGAUGCGGGUCACAGAGUACCUUGUCGUGUACACGCCCACCCACGAGGGUGGUCUGGAAAUGCAGUUCCGUGUGCCUGGGGACCAGACGUCCACCAUCAUCCAGGAGCUGGAGCCUGGUGUGGAGUACUUUAUCCGUGUAUUUGCCAUCCUGGAGAACAAGAAGAGCAUUCCUGUCAGCGCCAGGGUGGCCACGUACUUACCUGCACCUGAAGGCCUGAAAUUCAAGUCCAUCAAGGAGACAUCUGUGGAAGUGGAGUGGGAUCCUCUAGACAUUGCUUUUGAAACCUGGGAGAUCAUCUUCCGGAAUAUGAAUAAAGAAGAUGAGGGAGAGAUCACCAAAAGCCUGAGGAGGCCAGAGACCUCUUACCGGCAAACUGGUCUAGCUCCUGGGCAAGAGUAUGAGAUAUCUCUGCACAUAGUGAAAAACAAUACCCGGGGCCCUGGCCUGAAGAGGGUGACCACCACACGCUUGGAUGCCCCCAGCCAGAUCGAGGUGAAAGAUGUCACAGACACCACUGCCUUGAUCACCUGGUUCAAGCCCCUGGCUGAGAUCGAUGGCAUUGAGCUGACCUACGGCAUCAAAGACGUGCCAGGAGACCGUACCACCAUCGAUCUCACAGAGGACGAGAACCAGUACUCCAUCGGGAACCUGAAGCCUGACACUGAGUACGAGGUGUCCCUCAUCUCCCGCAGAGGUGACAUGUCAAGCAACCCAGCCAAAGAGACCUUCACAACAGGCCUCGAUGCUCCCAGGAAUCUUCGACGUGUUUCCCAGACAGAUAACAGCAUCACCCUGGAAUGGAGGAAUGGCAAGGCAGCUAUUGACAGUUACAGAAUUAAGUAUGCCCCCAUCUCUGGAGGGGACCACGCUGAGGUUGAUGUUCCAAAGAGCCAACAAGCCACAACCAAAACCACACUCACAGGUCUGAGGCCGGGAACUGAAUAUGGGAUUGGAGUUUCUGCUGUGAAGGAAGACAAGGAGAGCAAUCCAGCGACCAUCAACGCAGCCACAGAGUUGGACACGCCCAAGGACCUUCAGGUUUCUGAAACUGCAGAGACCAGCCUGACCCUGCUCUGGAAGACACCGUUGGCCAAAUUUGACCGCUACCGCCUCAAUUACAGUCUCCCCACAGGCCAGUGGGUGGGAGUGCAGCUUCCAAGAAACACCACUUCCUAUGUCCUGAGAGGCCUGGAACCAGGACAGGAGUACAAUGUCCUCCUGACAGCCGAGAAAGGCAGACACAAGAGCAAGCCCGCACGUGUGAAGGCAUCCACUGAACAAGCCCCUGAGCUGGAAAACCUCACCGUGACUGAGGUUGGCUGGGAUGGCCUCAGACUCAACUGGACCGCAGCUGACCAGGCCUAUGAGCACUUUAUCAUUCAGGUGCAGGAGGCCAACAAGGUGGAGGCAGCUCGGAACCUCACCGUGCCUGGCAGCCUUCGGGCUGUGGACAUACCGGGCCUCAAGGCUGCUACGCCUUAUACAGUCUCCAUCUAUGGGGUGAUCCAGGGCUAUAGAACACCAGUGCUCUCUGCUGAGGCCUCCACAGGGGAAACUCCCAAUUUGGGAGAGGUCGUGGUGGCCGAGGUGGGCUGGGAUGCCCUCAAACUCAACUGGACUGCUCCAGAAGGGGCCUAUGAGUACUUUUUCAUUCAGGUGCAGGAGGCUGACACAGUAGAGGCAGCCCAGAACCUCACCGUCCCAGGAGGACUGAGGUCCACAGACCUGCCUGGGCUCAAAGCAGCCACUCAUUAUACCAUCACCAUCCGCGGGGUCACUCAGGACUUCAGCACAACCCCUCUCUCUGUUGAAGUCUUGACAGAGGAGGUUCCAGAUAUGGGAAACCUCACAGUGACCGAGGUUAGCUGGGAUGCUCUCAGACUGAACUGGACCACGCCAGAUGGAACCUAUGACCAGUUUACUAUUCAGGUCCAGGAGGCUGACCAGGUGGAAGAGGCUCACAAUCUCACGGUUCCUGGCAGCCUGCGUUCCAUGGAAAUCCCAGGCCUCAGGGCUGGCACUCCUUACACAGUCACCCUGCACGGCGAGGUCAGGGGCCACAGCACUCGACCCCUUGCUGUAGAGGUCGUCACAGAGGAUCUCCCACAGCUGGGAGAUUUAGCCGUGUCUGAGGUUGGCUGGGAUGGCCUCAGACUCAACUGGACCGCAGCUGACAAUGCCUAUGAGCACUUUGUCAUUCAGGUGCAGGAGGUCAACAAAGUGGAGGCAGCCCAGAACCUCACGUUGCCUGGCAGCCUCAGGGCUGUGGACAUCCCGGGCCUCGAGGCUGCCACGCCUUAUAGAGUCUCCAUCUAUGGGGUGAUCCGGGGCUAUAGAACACCAGUACUCUCUGCUGAGGCCUCCACAGCCAAAGAACCUGAAAUUGGAAACUUAAAUGUUUCUGACAUAACUCCCGAGAGCUUCAAUCUCUCCUGGAUGGCUACCGAUGGGAUCUUCGAGACCUUUACCAUUGAAAUUAUUGAUUCCAAUAGGUUGCUGGAGACUGUGGAAUAUAAUAUCUCUGGUGCUGAACGAACUGCCCAUAUCUCAGGGCUACCCCCUAGUACUGAUUUUAUUGUCUACCUCUCUGGACUUGCUCCCAGCAUCCGGACCAAAACCAUCAGUGCCACAGCCACGACAGUAGCCAAACCUCUUCUUAGCCACCUCACUGUCUCAAACAUGACCUGGGGCAGUGUGUCCAUCUCGUGGGAAGCUCAGGAGUCUGCCUUUGAUAGCUUUCUUAUAGAAGUUAGUAAUUCCGAUCACCCCCAUGAGACCAUGGUGCUGUCUGUGCCUGGGGUGUCUCGCAGCUCUGUCAUCACCAACCUCAAAGCUUCUUCUAAUUACACUGCCCACCUUCAUGGGCUGAUUGGCGGGCAGCGUGCUCAGACCCUGAUGGUCCAAGCAACCACAGAACCAAAGCCACAGUUGGGCACGCUAAUCUUUAGCAAUAUUACUCCAAAAAGCUUCAACAUGUCAUGGACCACUCAAGCUGGGCUUUUUGCAAAGAUUGUUAUCAAUGUGAGUGACGCUCACUCACUGCAUGAGUCCCAGCAAUUCACAGUCUCAGGAGAUGCAAAGCAAGCUCACAUCACAGGCUUGGUGGAGAACACUGGCUAUGACGUCAGUGUGGCAGGAACCACCUUGGCUGGGGAUCCCACCAGACCCCUCACUGCCUUUGUCAUUACAGAGGCCCUGCCCCUUCUGGAAAACCUAACCAUUUCCGACAUUAAUCCCUACGGGUUCACAGUUUCCUGGAUGGCAUCGGAGAAUGCCUUUGACAGCUUUCUAGUAACGGUGGUGGAUUCUGGGAAGCUGCUGGACCCCCAGGAAUUCACACUUUCAGGAACCCAGAGGAAGCUGGAGCUUAGAGGCCUCAUAACUGGCAUUGGCUAUGAGGUUAUGGUCUCUGGCUUCACCCAAGGGCAUCAAACCAAGCCCUUGAGGGCUGAGAUUGUUACAGAAGCCGAACCGGAAGUUGACAACCUUCUGGUUUCAGAUGCCACCCCAGACGGUUUCCGUCUGUCCUGGACAGCUGAUGAAGGGGUCUUCGACAAUUUUGUUCUCAAAAUCAGAGAUACCAAAAAGCAGUCUGAGCCACUGGAAAUAACCCUACUUGCCCCCGAACGUACCAGGGACAUAACAGGUCUCAGAGAGGCUACUGAAUACGAAAUUGAACUCUAUGGAAUAAGCAAAGGAAGGCGAUCCCAGACAGUCAGUGCUAUAGCAACAACAGCCAUGGGCUCCCCAAAGGAAGUCAUUUUCUCAGACAUCACUGAAAAUUCGGCUACUGUCAGCUGGAGGGCACCCACAGCCCAAGUGGAGAGCUUCCGGAUUACCUAUGUGCCCAUUACAGGAGGUACACCCUCCAUGGUAACUGUGGACGGAACCAAGACUCAGACCAGGCUGGUGAAACUCAUACCUGGCGUGGAGUACCUUGUCAGCAUCAUCGCCAUGAAGGGCUUUGAGGAAAGUGAACCUGUCUCAGGGUCAUUCACCACAGCUCUGGAUGGCCCAUCUGGCCUGGUGACAGCCAACAUCACUGACUCAGAAGCCUUGGCCAGGUGGCAGCCAGCCAUUGCCACUGUGGACAGUUAUGUCAUCUCCUACACAGGCGAGAAAGUGCCAGAAAUUACACGCACGGUGUCCGGGAACACAGUGGAGUAUGCUCUGACCGACCUCGAGCCUGCCACGGAAUACACACUGAGAAUCUUUGCAGAGAAAGGGCCCCAGAAGAGCUCAACCAUCACUGCCAAGUUCACAACAGACCUCGAUUCUCCAAGAGACUUGACUGCUACUGAGGUUCAGUCGGAAACUGCCCUCCUUACCUGGCGACCCCCCCGGGCAUCAGUCACCGGUUACCUGCUGGUCUAUGAAUCAGUGGAUGGCACAGUCAAGGAAGUCAUUGUGGGUCCAGAUACCACCUCCUACAGCCUGGCAGACCUGAGCCCAUCCACCCACUACACAGCCAAGAUCCAGGCACUCAAUGGGCCCCUGAGGAGCAAUAUGAUCCAGACCAUCUUCACCACAAUUGGACUCCUGUACCCCUUCCCCAAGGACUGCUCCCAAGCAAUGCUGAAUGGAGACACGACCUCUGGCCUCUACACCAUUUAUCUGAAUGGUGAUAAGGCUGAGGCGCUGGAAGUCUUCUGUGACAUGACCUCUGAUGGGGGUGGAUGGAUUGUGUUCCUGAGACGCAAAAACGGACGCGAGAACUUCUACCAAAACUGGAAGGCAUAUGCUGCUGGAUUUGGGGACCGCAGAGAAGAAUUCUGGCUUGGGCUGGACAACCUGAACAAAAUCACAGCCCAGGGGCAGUACGAGCUCCGGGUGGACCUGCGGGACCAUGGGGAGACAGCCUUUGCUGUCUAUGACAAGUUCAGCGUGGGAGAUGCCAAGACUCGCUACAAGCUGAAGGUGGAGGGGUACAGUGGGACAGCAGGUGACUCCAUGGCCUACCACAAUGGCAGAUCCUUCUCCACCUUUGACAAGGACACAGAUUCAGCCAUCACCAACUGUGCUCUGUCCUACAAAGGGGCUUUCUGGUACAGGAACUGUCACCGUGUCAACCUGAUGGGGAGAUAUGGGGACAAUAACCACAGUCAGGGCGUUAACUGGUUCCACUGGAAGGGCCACGAACACUCAAUCCAGUUUGCUGAGAUGAAGCUGAGACCAAGCAACUUCAGAAAUCUUGAAGGCAGGCGCAAACGGGCAUAAAUUCCAGGGACCACUGGGUGAGAGAGGAAUAAGGCCCAGAGCGAGGAAAGGAUUUUACCAAAGCAUCAAUACAACCAGCCCAACCAUCGGUCCACACCUGGGCAUUUGGUGAGAGUCAAAGCUGACCAUGGAUCCCUGGGGCCAACGGCAACAGCAUGGGCCUCACCUCCUCUGUGAUUUCUUUCUUUGCACCAAAGACAUCAGUCUCCAACAUGUUUCUGUUUUGUUGUUUGAUUCAGCAAAAAUCUCCCAGUGACAACAUCGCAAUAGUUUUUUACUUCUCUUAGGUGGCUCUGGGAAUGGGAGAGGGGUAGGAUGUACAGGGGUAGUUUGUUUUAGAACCAGCCGUAUUUUACAUGAAGCUGUAUAAUUAAUUGUCAUUAUUUUUGUUAGCAAAGAUUAAAUGUGUCAUUGGAAGCCAUCCCUUUUUUUACAUUUCAUACAACAGAAACCAGAAAAGCAAUACUGUUUCCAUUUUAAGGAUAUGAUUAAUAUUAUUAAUAUAAUAAUGAUGAUGAUGAUGAUGAAAACUAAGGAUUUUUCAAGAGAUCUUUCUUUCCAAAACAUUUCUGGACAGUACCUGAUUGUAUUUUUUUUUUAAAUAAAAGCACAAGUACUUUUGAGUUUGUUAUUUUGCUUUGAAUUGUUGAGUCUGAAUUUCACCAAAGCCAAUCAUUUGAACAAAGCGGGGAAUGUUGGGAUAGGAAAGGUAAGUAGGGAUAGUGGUCAAGUGGGAGGGGUGGAAAGGAGACUAAAGACUGGGAGAGAGGGAAGCACUUUUUUUAAAUAAAGUUGAACACACUUGGGAAAAGCUUACAGGCCAGGCCUGUAAUCCCAACACUUUGGGAGGCCAAGGUGGGAGGAUAGCUUAACCCCAGGAGUUUGAGACCAGCCUGAGCAACAUAGUGAGAACUUGUCUCUACAGAAAAAAAAAAAAAAAAAAAUUUAAUUAGGCAAGCGUGGUAGUGCGCACCUGUCGUCCCAGCUACUCAGGAGGCUGAGGUAGGAAAAUCACUGGAGCCCAGGAGUUAGAGGUUACAGUGAGCUAUGAUCACACUACUGCACUCCAGCCUGGGCAACAGAGGGAGACCCUGUCUCUAAAUAAAAAAAGAAAAGAAAAAAAAAGCUUACAACUUGAGAUUCAGCAUCUUGCUCAGUAUUUCCAAGACUAAUAGAUUAUGGUUUAAAAGAUGCUUUUAUACUCAUUUUCUAAUGCAACUCCUAGAAACUCUAUGAUAUAGUUGAGGUAAGUAUUGUUACCACACAUGGGCUAAGAUCCCCAGAGGCAGACUGCCUGAGUUCAAUUCUUGGCUCCACCAUUCCCAAGUUCCCUAACCUCUCUAUGCCUCAGUUUCCUCUUCUGUAAAGUAGGGACACUCAUACUUCUCAUUUCAGAACAUUUUUGUGAAGAAUAAAUUAUGUUAUCCAUUUGAGGCCCUUAGAAUGGUACCCGGUGUAUAUUAAGUGCUAGUACAUGUUAGCUAUCAUCAUUAUCACUUUAUAUGAGAUGGACUGGGGUUCAUAGAAACCCAAUGACUUGAUUGUGGCUACUACUCAAUAAAUAAUAGAAUUUGGAUUUAAA